AUGGCCUGUUCCGUCAUGGUGGCAGGGCGGGCAGCGGAACGGGAGGACAGCCGGAGAACGGGCGCGGAGAGUGAAUGGAGGGCGUCGCUGGCUCAGCCCUGCCGCCGCCUGGACCGAAAGGACGGAGCAGCCACCGCGCAGCCGCUAAGACGCCGACGCCACGCCCACUCUCCGCCCCCGCGCCUCCUCGCGCCGCGCUCAUUGGCUGCGCCGCCAGGCCCCGCCCCACACCAGCCUGCGUGCCUCGCCUCUGAGGGCUGCCGGGAAUCCCGCUGCGUCCCGCCCCGCACUCCAGCGAACCGCGCCCAUUGGCUGCGCUCCCCGGAGACGUCCCGCCCCGCACCCCUAGCCUCAGCGAGGCCGGGCUGGACGGGGCCCUGGUGCUGGUUUUCAGUGCCUCAGCGAGGCCGGGACCAGAGCUGCUAUUUCCAGAUGAGGCUGGCUCGCAUCUGCUCUGGCCGGGGCUCCAGGCCUGAGCCCUGCAACACGGCGUUCCCUUUCCAAGUCUGCAAAGCCUGUCUUAGGGGAGAGAAGAAGUUUCCUUCCAUGCGGGUGGGGACGGCUAACCAUGUCCAGACACUGAGACCGGUGCUCUGUGUGCUCAGCCUUCAGCCUGCACUGGCUUGGUGGCUUGGUGACCCGCCAGCAGGGUGGUGCUGUCUGUGGGCUCUGCUCAAGCUCCUCUCAGAGCCAGGAGGAUGCCCGCCUGCUUGGGCCUGGCUCCCAGGAUGUGCUUGGCAAAUGCUUCUGGGAUGGAUGGAUGGAUGGAGUGCUGCACGUGGGACUUAGCCUUGGACACUAACUCCUUUGCCCCUCGUAUCUGGGAGGGAACAACACAGUUGCUAUGCCUGACUAGGGCAUGACCUGGGAGGCCUUUGGGGCCACACAGCCUCCUUGGGAAAGGAGGAUCAGGUGGGCCUCACACCCAGGAAUUGGAAGUGGGAGAGACAACAGCUGCUGGGUAGUGGGGGUAGAGCUGUGUCUCUCACUGCCCUGCCCCUCCAAGGACCAAGAAGAAAGGAAUGAGCCCCGAUCCGCCUGCCAGGUACCCACCCAUGAGAACCCCUUCUCUGCCAGCAUCUGAUAAAAUUACCUGCGUAGCUUUAGAGAUCACUGCUGCCUGACCAGCAGCCGCUCUGCUGGAAUCUGUCCAGAAAGCCCCUUGGGGCUCAGAAAAGUAGGUGGGUUAAUAAUAGAAGUAGAUGUGGGUUUUUUUGUUUGUGUGUUUAUUGAGACGGAGUCUUGCUCUGUGGCCCAGGCUGGAGUGCAGUGGCGUGA